GCAUUGGACAGACAGAGAGUGAAAGAGAGGGCGAGGGAGAGGGAGAGAAGGAGAGAGAAGGGGGGAGCAGAGAAGAGAGAAGAGAGAGGGAGGGAGGGAGAGCGAGAACAGGAGGAGAGAACAGAGGCAAAGAAGAGAGGAAAAAGGGAGAAAGGAGAGAGAAAGAGAAAGAAGUGCCGCUGCAGAUAAUUGAUUACACCGCGAUCAAGGCUAACUUGUUAGCAAUAGUCAAUUGCCCCGUCUCUCCGCCUCCCUCGCAGUCCGGGAUCGGCGCCCUCGCCUCGGCUCUUCCAACUGCGGCCGCCAGGACCCGGGGCCAGGAGCCACUGCCGAGCCACCUGACACCUUUAAAUAGCACCGGGGUUGGCGAAACUGGAGCCCCGCGCAGCGCGCCCCGGCUCCGGCCCCGGAUUGCUGGAAGCCCCAGCAGCAGCGGCGCCCGCGUCAGCGCCCUCUUCCCGGGGCCCCGCGCUGUUCUCCCCUCCUCAGCCGCCGCGCUAAUCGGCCCCGCGCCCGGCCCGCGCCCUGCCCAGUGCGGCCUCCUUUCCACCCGCCGCUGCCUGCCCGCGCCGUCCGGCGCCCGAGCUGCCCGCGGGCUGGGUCCCCGCGGCCCGAGCCGCCCCGGCCGGGACCCCGAACAAGGCCGAGAUGACUUCCAAGGAGGACGGCAAGGCGGCGCCGGGGGAGGAGCGGCGGCGCAGCCCGCUGGACCACCUGCCUCCGCCUGCCAACUCCAACAAGCCACUGACGCCGUUCAGCAUCGAGGACAUCCUCAACAAGCCGUCUGUGCGGAGAAGUUACUCGCUGUGCGGGGCGGCGCACCUGCUGGCCGCCGCGGACAAGCACGCGCAGGGCGGCUUGCCCCUGGCGGGCCGCGCGCUGCUCUCGCAGACCUCGCCGCUGUGCGCGCUGGAGGAGCUCGCCAGCAAGACGUUUAAGGGGCUGGAGGUCAGCGUUCUGCAGGCAGCCGAAGGCCGCGACGGUAUGACCAUCUUUGGGCAGCGGCAGACCCCUAAGAAGCGGCGAAAGUCGCGCACGGCCUUCACCAACCACCAGAUCUAUGAAUUGGAAAAGCGCUUUCUAUACCAGAAGUACCUGUCCCCCGCCGAUCGCGACCAAAUCGCGCAGCAGCUGGGCCUCACCAACGCGCAAGUCAUCACCUGGUUCCAGAAUCGGCGCGCUAAGCUCAAGCGGGACCUGGAGGAGAUGAAGGCCGACGUAGAGUCCGCCAAGAAACUGGGCCCCAGCGGGCAGAUGGACAUCGUGGCGCUGGCCGAACUCGAGCAGAACUCGGAGGCCACAGCCGGCGGUGGCGGCGGCUGCGGCAGGGCCAAGUCGAGGCCCGGCUCUCCGGUCCUCCCCCCAGGCGCCCCGAAGGCCCCGGGCGCUGGCGCCCUGCAGCUCUCGCCUGCCUCUCCGCUCACGGACCAGCCGGCCAGCAGCCAGGACUGCUCGGAGGACGAGGAAGACGAAGAGAUCGACGUGGACGAUUGAGCGGCGCCCCGGGUCUUCCGCCGCCCUGGGCUCCUAGCGCUCGAAAGCCCAACGCCUCCCGGACCGGACCGCCGAGGGGAGCUGGGACCUCCUCUGCCAACUCCCGCCUCCUCCCCUGUCCCCGGCCCCGGACUCGGCUCCUGGCAGCCGCCUCUUCCCUCUCGAAGCAAUAAACCCAGGCUGGCCGGCCGGGCCGGCCGCCACCAGCGGCCUCCGCCGCCCCGGAAGCCCUCGCCGUGCAAUUCUGUAUGGCUUCUAUAUAAAUAUUUAAACCUA